AGACUACUUCUGUACAGCGUGUGAAGUGUCCCGCAAGCACGUAUAACCUUAAAAUAGCAACAAGGGCAGCAGCAACAACGACAACAAAAAUGAUAAUGGCAAAGAGAAGCAGAACCUAAUGUUUUUUGGGUUUGCCCACUGAUACCCUUUUAAUCCUGAUUUUUAAUUGUUUGGCACAAAGAUAUGUAAUAAUUUCUUGGGUCUUCUGGGCAUUUAAAUGUCAUUUUGGUUUCACCAAAUGUAUUUAUGAUUCCACCUACACAUGCUCUUUUAAGACACUUACUCUUCCAUCAUGAGAACAUACCUGUGAAUAGAACCACCUUUUAAAGUGCACUUGCAUUCUGACACUUCUACCUCUGAACAGUGCAGAUGAGAUUUAUGAGCUACGUGUAACCGGACGUACCCAGGAUGAGAUUUUAUUCUCUAAUAGUACCCGCUUAUCAUUUGAGACCAAGAGAAUAUCUGUCUUCAUUCAAACAGACAAGGCCUUAUACAAGCCAAAGCAAGAAGUGAAGUUUCGCAUUGUUACACUCUUCUCAGAUUUUAAGCCUUACAAAACCUCUUUAAACAUUCUCAUUAAGGACCCCAAAUCAAAUUUGAUCCAACAGUGGUUGUCACAACAAAGUGAUCUUGGAGUCAUUUCCAAAACUUUUCAGCUAUCUUCCCAUCCAAUACUUGGUGACUGGUCUAUUCAAGUUCAAGUGAAUGACCAGACAUACUAUCAAUCAUUUCAGGUUUCAGAAUAUGUAUUACCAAAAUUUGAAGUGACUUUGCAGACACCAUUAUAUUGUUCUAUGAAUUCUAAGCAUUUAAAUGGUACCAUCACGGCAAAGUAUACAUAUGGGAAGCCAGUGAAAGGAGACGUAACGCUUACAUUUUUACCUUUAUCCUUUUGGGGAAAGAAGAAAAAUAUUACAAAAACAUUUAAGAUAAAUGGAUCUGCAAACUUCUCUUUUAAUGAUGAAGAGAUGAAAAAUGUAAUGGAUUCUUCAAAUGGACUUUCUGAAUACCUGGAUCUAUCUUCCCCUGGACCAGUAGAAAUUUUAACCACAGUGACAGAAUCAGUUACAGGUAUUUCAAGAAAUGUAAGCACUAAUGUGUUCUUCAAGCAACAUGAUUACAUCAUUGAGUUUUUUGAUUAUACUACUGUCUUGAAGCCAUCUCUCAACUUCACAGCCACUGUGAAGGUAACUCGUGCUGAUGGCAACCAACUGACUCUUGAAGAAAGAAGAAAUAAUGUAGUCAUAACAGUGACACAGAGAAACUAUACUGAGUACUGGAGCGGAUCUAACAGUGGAAAUCAGAAAAUGGAAGCUGUUCAGAAAAUAAAUUAUACUGUCCCCCAAAGUGGAACUUUUAAGAUUGAAUUCCCAAUCCUGGAGGAUUCCAGUGAGCUACAGUUGAAGGCCUAUUUCCUUGGUAGUAAAAGUAGCAUGGCAGUUCAUAGUCUGUUUAAGUCUCCUAGUAAGACAUACAUCCAACUAAAAACAAGAGAUGAAAAUAUAAAGGUGGGAUCGCCUUUUGAGUUGGUGGUUAGUGGCAACAAACGAUUGAAGGAGUUAAGCUAUAUGGUAGUAUCCAGGGGACAGUUGGUGGCUGUAGGAAAACAAAAUUCAACAAUGUUCUCUUUAACACCAGAAAAUUCUUGGACUCCAAAAGCCUGUGUAAUUGUGUAUUAUAUUGAAGAUGAUGGGGAAAUUAUAAGUGAUGUUCUAAAAAUUCCUGUUCAGCUUGUUUUUAAAAAUAAGAUAAAGCUAUAUUGGAGUAAAGUGAAAGCUGAACCAUCUGAGAAAGUCUCUCUUAGGAUCUCUGUGACACAGCCUGACUCCAUAGUUGGGAUUGUAGCUGUUGACAAAAGUGUGAAUCUGAUGAAUGCCUCUAAUGAUAUUACAAUGGAAAAUGUGGUCCAUGAGUUGGAACUUUAUAACACAGGAUAUUAUUUAGGCAUGUUCAUGAAUUCUUUUGCAGUCUUUCAGGAAUGUGGACUCUGGGUAUUGACAGAUGCAAACCUCACGAAGGAUUAUAUUGAUGGUGUUUAUGACAAUGCAGAAUAUGCUGAGAGGUUUAUGGAGGAAAAUGAAGGACAUAUUGUAGAUAUUCAUGACUUUUCUUUGGGUAGCAGUCCACAUGUCCGAAAGCAUUUUCCAGAGACUUGGAUUUGGCUAGACACCAACAUGGGUUACAGGAUUUACCAAGAAUUUGAAGUAACUGUACCUGAUUCUAUCACUUCUUGGGUGGCUACUGGUUUUGUGAUCUCUGAGGACCUGGGUCUUGGACUAACAACUACUCCAGUGGAGCUCCAAGCCUUCCAACCAUUUUUCAUUUUUUUGAAUCUUCCCUACUCUGUUAUCAGAGGUGAAGAAUUUGCUUUGGAAAUAACUAUAUUCAAUUAUUUGAAAGAUGCCACUGAGGUUAAGGUAAUCAUUGAGAAAAGUGACAAAUUUGAUAUUCUAAUGACUUCAAAUGAAAUAAAUGCCACAGGCCACCAGCAGACCCUUCUGGUUCCCAGUGAGGAUGGGGCAACUGUUCUUUUUCCCAUCAGGCCAACACAUCUGGGAGAAAUUCCUAUCACAGUCACAGCUCUUUCACCCACUGCUUCUGAUGCUGUCACCCAGAUGAUUUUAGUAAAGGCUGAAGGAAUAGAAAAAUCAUAUUCACAAUCCAUCUUAUUAGACUUGACUGACAAUAGGCUACAGAGUACCCUGAAAACUUUGAGUUUCUCAUUUCCUCCUAAUACAGUGACUGGCAGUGAAAGAGUUCAGAUCACUGCAAUUGGAGAUGUUCUUGGUCCUUCCAUCAAUGGCUUAGCCUCAUUGAUUCGGAUGCCUUAUGGCUGUGGUGAACAGAACAUGAUAAAUUUUGCUCCAAAUAUUUACAUUUUGGAUUAUCUGACUAAAAAGAAACAACUGACAGAUAAUUUGAAAGAAAAAGCUCUUUCAUUUAUGAGGCAAGGUUACCAGAGAGAACUUCUCUAUCAGAGGGAAGAUGGCUCUUUCAGUGCUUUUGGGAAUUAUGACCCUUCUGGGAGCACUUGGUUGUCAGCUUUUGUUUUAAGAUGUUUCCUUGAAGCCGAUCCUUACAUAGAUAUUGAUCAGAAUGUGUUACACAGAACAUACACUUGGCUUAAAGGACAUCAGAAAUCCAACGGUGAAUUUUGGGAUCCAGGAAGAGUGAUUCAUAGUGAGCUUCAAGGUGGCAAUAAAAGUCCAGUAACACUUACAGCCUAUAUUGUAACUUCUCUCCUGGGAUAUAGAAAGUAUCAGCCUAACAUUGAUGUGCAAGAGUCUAUCCAUUUUUUGGAGUCUGAAUUCAGUAGAGGAAUUUCAGACAAUUAUACUCUAGCCCUUAUAACUUAUGCAUUGUCAUCAGUGGGGAGUCCUAAAGCGAAGGAAGCUUUGAAUAUGCUGACUUGGAGAGCAGAACAAGAAGGUGGCAUGCAAUUCUGGGUGUCAUCAGAGUCCAAACUUUCUGACUCCUGGCAGCCACGCUCCCUGGAUAUUGAAGUUGCAGCCUAUGCACUGCUCUCACACUUCUUACAAUUUCAGACUUCUGAGGGAAUCCCAAUUAUGAGGUGGCUAAGCAGGCAAAGAAAUAGCUUGGGUGGUUUUGCAUCUACUCAGGAUACCACUGUGGCUUUAAAGGCUCUGUCUGAAUUUGCAGCCCUAAUGAAUACAGAAAGGACAAAUAUCCAAGUGACCGUGACGGGGCCUAGCUCACCAAGUCCUGUAAAGUUUCUGAUUGACACACACAACCGCUUACUCCUUCAGACAGCAGAGCUUGCUGUGGUACAGCCAACGGCAGUUAAUAUUUCCGCAAAUGGUUUUGGAUUUGCUAUUUGUCAGCUCAAUGUUGUAUAUAAUGUGAAGGCUUCUGGGUCUUCUAGAAGACGAAGAUCUAUCCAAAAUCAAGAAGCCUUUGAUUUAGAUGUUGCUGUAAAAGAAAAUAAAGAUGAUCUCAAUCAUGUGGAUUUGAAUGUGUGUACAAGCUUUUCGGGCCCGGGUAGGAGUGGCAUGGCUCUUAUGGAAGUUAACCUAUUAAGUGGCUUUAUGGUGCCUUCAGAAGCAAUUUCUCUGAGCGAGACAGUGAAGAAAGUGGAAUAUGAUCAUGGAAAACUCAACCUCUAUUUAGAUUCUGUAAAUGAAACCCAGUUUUGUGUUAAUAUUCCUGCUGUGAGAAACUUUAAAGUUUCAAAUACCCAAGAUGCUUCAGUGUCCAUAGUGGAUUACUAUGAGCCAAGGAGACAGGCGGUGAGAAGUUACAACUCUGAAGUGAAGCUGUCCUCCUGUGACCUUUGCAGUGAUGUCCAGGGCUGCCGUCCUUGUGAGGAUGGAGCUUCAGGCUCCCAUCAUCACUCUUCAGUCAUUUUUAUUUUCUGUUUCAAGCUUCUGUACUUUAUGGAACUUUGGCUGUGAUUUAUUUUUAAAGGACUCUGUGUAACACUAACAUUUCCAGUAGUCACAUGUGAUUGUUUUGUUUUCGUAGAAGAAUACUGCUUCUAUUUUGAAAAAAGAGUUUUUUUUCUUUCUAUGGGGUUGCAGGGAUGGUGUACAACAGGUCCUAGCAUGUAUAGCUGCAUAGAUUUCUUCACCUGAUCUUUGUGUGGAAGAUCAGAAUGAAUGCAGUUGUGUGUCUAUAUUUUCCCCUCUCAAAAUCUUUUAGAAUUUUUUUGGAGGUGUUUGUUUUCUCCAGAAUAAAGGUAUUACUUUAGAAUAGGUAUUCUCCUCAUUUUGUGAAAGAAAUGAACCUAGAUUCUUAAGCAUUAUUACACAUCCAUGUUUGCUUAAAGAUGGAUUUCCCUGGGAAUGGGAGAAAACAGCCAGCAGGAGGAGCUUCAUCUGUUCCCUUCCCACCUCCAACCUAGCCCUACUGCCCACCCCACCCCAACCCACCCCAUGCCCAGUGGUCUCAGUAGAUACUUCUUAACUGGAAAUUCUUUCUUUUCAGAAUCUAGGUGGUGAAUUUUUUUUAAGUGGCACGGUCUUUUUCUGCUUGAAAUCUGAUCACACCCCCCAGCCAUUGCCCUCCCUCUCUUUUUCCUCUGUAGAGAAAUGUGAGGGGCAGUACAUUUACUGUGCUUUUCACACCAUCUCAGAGGUUGAGGAGCAUACUGAAAAUUGCCCUGGGGGGUGCUGGGUGUGCUGUCUCCUUCCCACAUCCUCAGCCCCACACCAGCUCUAUUUCAGGGGUGAGAGUCAGAGAGCACUGCAAUAUGUGCUUCAUGGGAUUUCGAUUCGAAGAUCCUAGACCAGGGAGACACUGUGAGCCAGGGAUACAACAAAAUACUAGGUAAGUCACUGCAGACCGACCUCCCUGCAGUUUGGGAAAGAAGCUGGGUUUGUGGAGAAUCAGAGCAUCUUGACAUGACUGCUGACCUAAAGAUCCCUGGCAUUGGCCAGGGAUCCUGUGGAACCUCUUCUAGUUCAGGGGUGUGAGCAUUAGACUGCCAGUUGUCUAGUGACAUCUGAUGCUUGCUGUGAACUUUUAAGAUCCCCGAAUCCUGAGCACCUCAAUCUUUAAUUGCCCUGUAUUCCGAAGGGUAAUAUAAUUUAUCUGGAUGGAAAUUUUAAAGAUGAAUCCCCCUUUUUUCUUUUCUUCUCUCUUUUCUUUCCUUCUCCCUUUCUUCUUUGCCUUCUAAAUAUACUGAAAUGAUUUAGAUAUGUGUCAACAAUUAAUGAUCUUUUAUUCAAUCUAAGAAAUGGUUUAGUUUUUCUCUUUAGCUCUAUGGCAUUUCACUCAAGUGGACAGGGGAAAAAGUAAUUGCCAUGGGCUCCAAAGAAUUUGCUUUAUGUUUUUAGCUAUUUAAAAAUAAAUCCAUCAAAAAUAAAGUAUGCAAAUGUAUCUUUUAAAGUUAAUUUUUAAAAAUGCUCUUAUUUUAGUGAAUUUUCAGAAAUUAUAGUGGAAUGGAUGCUCAUAUAUUGCUUAUGGAUAUUUUGGAUACCAAAGUAGGAAUAACUGACAUUCAGUAUUUUAAAGCUGGCAAACCUGUACAUAGAAAAUAGAUCCCCAGACAGUGGUCUAUGAAGAGGGCAGUUAAGUAUCAAAUACUUAAUUUUCUUGCCUUUUUUUCUUAAGUGGGGAAAAGUUUCUAGAUCUCUUACACCUCUGACACAAUCUGUUCUAAAACAGGCACUUGUAAUGUUGGGGCCUCCUUGUAAACGUGUUUUUGCCCUUUACUCUCUGGGAGUUCUUUAAAGGUGAAAUCAUCUUACAAAGAAAUUGGGGGAGGGUCUUGGCAAAGGACUUUCCCCUCCUCUUUCCUGGCCUGGGAACCUUAUACUGACAAUCAAUACUUUAUAUUUUAAAGUAUAUAAUUUAUAGUUAACUUCUAGUGUAAUAUAUUAGGAAACACUAGAAUGGAAAGGCCAUUGGAAGACAGGUUGUAUCUUUUUUAGACCAUAUUUCCUUGUUUAAAAACUAUCAUUUGAAUACUUUUUUGGUGAAGAACUCCAUGUUUUCAAGUUAAAGGUCACCUCGUAGGCCAGGCGCAGUGGCUCAUGCCUGUAAUCCCAGCACUCUGGGAGGCUGAGGCGGGUGAAUCACAAGGUUAGGAGUUUGAGACCAGCCUGGCCAAUAUGGUGAAACCCCGUCCCUACUAAAAAUACAAAAUUUAGCCAGGCGUGGUGGCAUGCACCUGUAGUCCCACCUACUCGGGAGGCUGAGGCAGGAGAAUCACUUGAACCUGAGAGACAGAGGUUGCAGUGAGCCGAGAUCACGCCACUGCACUCCAGCCUGGGGGACAGAGUGAGAUUCUGUCUCAAAAAACAAAAAACAAAAAAGUCACCUUGUAACUCAUCUCUUUUUAUUGUAAGUUUAUUAAAAAUGAAGAGGACAACAAUGAGAAGGAACAUAAAGGGUUAGCUAGCACUGUCUCCUGGUGCAUGGGGCUGUGCAGAUGUCCCGGCCACUUCUUCCUUCAUACUUCCCUUAGAGAACUUGCUCUGCUACAAGCAGUGGGCUUGGACUAAAAGUGAUUAAAAUACCACAGGCAUAAGGAGAAAAGGAGUAUAUGUAGUAGUAAUAAUUACUAGUAUAAAUUAUUUUCUUCACAUGCUAUGAGUAAUAAUAUUAAAAAACUCAUUUUACCAUUAAGAUUCCUUAUGCUGAAGCUCUUCCAUUUAGAAUACUGUCAAUGUCAUUUACUGGUAUGAACUAAAGUCCCCCUUCUUUUCCACUCACUGGGAACCUUAGUAAAACACCAGCAUAUCUUACCUCUCUUUCUGACUGGCCGAUGCUUCCAGAGACUGAAUGUUGGGAAAACCUAGUAGCCAAACAAUUCUAGGACAGAAUAACAUUUUUAUAUUUGGUUCCACCAUCUUAUUACAUUUAGUUAUAGUUUUAAAAAAGAAAUUCAAGCCCAUUAAAAUAUGUCUGGUCAAUGAAAUGCUUCCUUUUAUUGUGUUGUGCUAUUGUACUUUGUUUUUCAAAACAUUGUAAAAAUAGUAUCUUUGGUUUAGUAUUUUGGAUUAUAUAUUAUAAUCUGAGGAGUGUUUUGCUUAUGUAGAAUCCAGAUAUAUUUCUGUUACCUAGGAGAUGUUACUUACAUAUGUAAUACUGUAUCCUGCACGUGGAAAUAUUCAGAAUUGUAGAUAGCAUAACUCUCCCUGCUCCUAUUCUUUUGAGCCUAGGUAUAAUUUUUUUUUUUUUUUUAGAAAAAGACAUAUUUAGCUUUAAUUUCUAUUUAUGCUAAACAUAUUUAUAAGUAGUCUGUCAAUAUAAUACCAACUAUUUUUAUUUUUACAUAAUUCAAUUAUUUCAUUUGACAUGUCUGGCAGACUCAAGACAUUAAGUAAAAAAUUGGAACUAUGAUUUUUCUUUGUCAUUUUUUAAAAAAGAAUUAUUUUAUUAACCUGCUGGCAUAUAAUCUGGAGUUCUUUUCACAACCUUACUUUUUCUGAUUUGCUUUAUUGAAUGAUUGAAUACUCAUUUCUUUCUAAAAAUAUGUUGUAAAUUCUCCCUUGGCAAGAUUUCUCCCUAUGAGGGUAGUUAUUAUUUGAGUCUGCCAAGUGGUUACCAUGGGGCAAGGUGCCAUGAUGUAUUCUUGGGUGCAUUGGUUUUUUGCGCAUUGUAAAUUUAAGACACUUAUAGUAAGUGGACUCAUUCAUAGAUGAGUUUCAGAACCUUUUACGUUCUCGGUAGAGGCUUCUGUCGGACAGGCAGAAGAGUGUAUUCCUCACUUUUUUUUUUGUCUUCAAAUUCCAGUAAGGCAUAGCACUUUUAAGAAAUUAGAAUUUUUCUAUCAUCUAUGCAAAUGAUAUUUAUGUUAAUAUUAAAUAUCUUAUGUUACACUGGGAGUAAUUUGAGGUGCAAUUAUUUUUAUUACUACUUUGAAUAGAGGACCAUUAUCCUUCUUUCUUCAGAAAACUAAGAAGUAAGUGUAACUUUUAAAGUAAGUAUAUAUCAGUGAGAGUAGGCUUGUUUUACAACUAUUUCUAGCCAGUGAGUUGUGUUUUCAUGUCUCAUCAAAAGACAAUACCACAUUGCAUCAUUUUACAAAAUAUGUUGUCAUUUUCAUUUCAGUUGUAACAUAGGAAAAUAGAUAUUUCCUAGAUGAUUUCUGAGUUUCUUACUGCAAAGAACAGUUAUAAAUUGGUAUACAUGUGUCUCUGUAAUAGGGAUAAUAUUGAUAUAUCUGUUGCUACAUAUUUAAGAAUCAUUCUAUCUUAUGUUGUCUUGAGGCCAAGAUUUACCACGUUUGCCCAGUGUAUUGAAUUGGUGGUAGAAGGUAGUUCCAUGUUCCAUUUGUAGAUCUUUAAGAUUUUAUCUUUGAUAACUUUAAUAGAAUGUGGCUCAGUUCUGGUCCUUCAAGCCUGUAUGGUUUGGAUUUUCAGUAGGGGACAGUUGAUGUGGAGUCAAUCUCUUUGGUACACAGGAAGCUUUAUAAAAUUUCAUUCACGAAUCUCUUAUUUUGGGAAGCUGUUUUGCAUAUGAGAAGAACACUGUUGAAAUAAGGAACUAAAGCUUUAUAUAUUGAUCAAGGUGAUUCUGAAAGUUUUAAUUUUUAAUGUUGUAAUGUUAUGUUAUUGUUAAUUGUACUUUAUUAUGUAUUCAAUAGAAAAUCAUGAUUUAUUAAUAAAAGCUUAAAUUCUCAUCUA